CGUCGGAGCCUGCGGGAGGGUGGUGGUGGUGGUGGUGGUGGCCUCGCCCGCCUCACUCAUGCCUCCUCCUCCUCUGCUCUCGCUCAGGCGCCUCGGUGGCGGUUGGUCGGCGGUUAGCGCGGCUGGUGGUCGCGGCGGCCGGGGCUCGCUCUCGGGGAGGCCGGGGCGGAUCUCGCGGCGCAGGCGGCGGCGGCCGAGGUGGGGUCGCGCGGCGGAGGCGGCUCGAGCUUCGUGCUGCGCGCUCUCUCUUGGGCUCCUCGCUCGAUCUUACUGCCCCAAAAAUGGCCCCGCACAAGUUUUUCUAGGCGGCGCACCGGCCCGGGAGGGAAGGGCGGGCGAGGGGAGAGGGUGGGGAAACUUGGCUCGGGAGUCGGGCCCUGGACUCUCAUUAGCAUUUAAAGGCGCCCGGUGCGCUUUCUAUGGCUCCAAUCCGCCGGGACGCGAGCGCGCGGGUCGCGUUGCAGAACCAAGGAAAGCCAGGGUGAACGGGGCGCCCGGGUUGUCUUCUGGAGCGUUCCGAGGAGCCCGCGCUGCUGACCCUUUGUUGGAGCGGGGUGCAUUGGCUCUCCUCCCUCAACCCGUCUUGACACCCGCAGCUGACAAGGAGAGAAUUACAUUACAAGAAAAAAAAGUAAGGAGAUUGAACUCUUCAAACCGAUCCAACAGUAAAGCCUUUUAAAAAAAUUCAUCCUUGGAAGUAAUUCAUAACUAACAGGUGUGAUCUCCAACCUCUGGAAGACCCUAAAAUAAUUACAGAUGCACCCUGGGAUUUCCUAGAAUUUGUGCUGGACUGGCUUCCAAAACUACUCAUCAUUGUCAUCCAAACAAAGCAGUGAGCAGCUGGAAGUUGUUGGUAUUGUACUAAAUAAAUCUAAAGAAAAUUAGAACAAA